ACUUGUCCUUUGCCUUCGCUAUAGUCAGCUUCAGCAGCAGACUUAGGAGCCCUGGUCCCUCUCCAGCCCACUUCUGUCUCUGCAGGUGCAACUCCUGCGUGAUCUGGUCCUCAGGAAACUGGCAACAUAGACUUUUAGAAAAUAUUGUCCUAAGCACAUUAACACAGGAACAGAAAACCAAAUGCUGCAUUUUCUCACUUAUAAGUGGAGCUAAAUAUCAGGUCCUCAUGGACAUAAAGAUGGCAACAGUAGACACUGGGGACUGCUAGAGUGGGGAGGGAGGGAGGCAGAGUUGAAAAACUGUUGGGAACUAUGCUCAGUACCCAGGUGAUGGGAUCACCCCUACCCAAAUCACGCAGUAUACCCAGGUAGCAAACCUGCACAUGUACCCCCCGAAUCUAAAAUAAAAGUUGAAGCAGAAAAAAAGCAAACAAUACAGUAAAAAGAAAAAAGAAAAAUUGAAGGAGUCUCUCAGAUACCGAGGGUAACACGCAGGCACCUACAUGCUCACUCAUCUGGUUUAAGAAAUAACACAUUUCCAAUCAGUUGAAAUUUCUCCUUCAUCAGCCACCAACAAGAAACAAGUGUUCUGAAUUUAGUGGGGUUUUUUUCUUGCAUUUCUUUAAAGUUUUUUUUUUAAUGUGUGCAUCCCUAAAUAAUACAUAGUAUUUUUUUAUGUUUAAAAAUGUUAUUUAGGCUGAGCGUGGUGACUCAUGCCUUACUGGCACUUUGGGAGGCAGAGCAGGCAGGUGGAUCUCUUGAGCCCAGGAGUUUGAGACCAGCUUGGGCAACAUGGCCAAAACCCAUCUCUGCAAACAAUACAAAAAUUAGCUGGGUGUGGUGGCGCAUGCCUGUAGUUCCAGCUACUUGAGAGGCUAAGGUGGGAGGAUGACUUGGGCUGGGAGGUGGAAGUUGCAGUGAACUGAGAUCAUGCCACUGCACUCCAGCCUGGGCAACAGAGUGAGACCCAGAUUCAUUCAUGUUCGUAUCUCCAGCUGUGGCUCAUUCUUUUUUCACUGCUGUAUAGUAUUUCCUGAUAGGAAAUUGCCACAAUGUAUUUAUUCAUUUUUCUCUUCAUUUUAGGUAGCUUUCAGCUUUUUGUUGUUAACACAAGGCAUCUUUGGCUUUCAUCUGAGUACCUCAGCCCCUGUCCAGCCCCUUUUCCUUCCUAGCUCCUUGGCAGCCAUUACUGCUCCUGUCUGGGUAGCAUUUUAAGGUUUACAGAGAACUCUAUGGUUCCUACUUGGUCCUCAUAACAUUUCCAUAGGGAGAAACAAGGAAAGUGAGGCCUACCCAGGGUCAUUCGAGAAGGGAUCAUAGCCAGGAUUUGAAUCUGUGAAACCCUCUUUCCACCAUAUUUUGUAUAAGAGGAAUUCCCCAAAAUUGGCAUCUUACCUCUUGGAGGCAGGGGAGUUACAGGGUUAGAUAAACUCUGGUUUCAGGCCAUCCUCCUGCGUCUGUCUCUGGAGUAGCUGGGACUACAGGCAUGCACCACUGCACUCAGCUCACUUAAAUUUUUUAGAAAAAUAUUUUAAAAUUUCCCUUUAAAAAAAAUUACCAAAUAGCACAUGAUUAUUGGGGAAAAACCCCCCAAAACUCAAGCAGUACAAAAGAUAUAAUGUAAAAAAUGACAGUUGUCUUCUCUCUCCUUCCUUUCCCCUUCCUCUGUCCCUACUGUAUUUAAAAACUAAUUUUAUAAUUGUAUAAGAACAGGACUAGAUUUCCCAUGUAAAGAGUUAAAAUAGCAUAGGUAAAAUAAAAGUUUCUUUUGGUUUUAGUUCCUUACCGAGGUCCUUCUGUAGAGCAGUCUACUAGUAGCAGUUUGGUAUGUAUCCUUUGAGACUUUUUUCUUUUCUUCUUUUCUUUUUUUUAAGAGACAGAGUAUUAGUCUGUCACUCAGGCUGGAGUUCAGUGGCAUGAUCAUAGCUCACUGUAGCCUGAACUGCUGGGCUCAAGUGAUCCUCCCACCUCAACUUUCCGAGUAGCUGGGACUCCAGGCAUGUGCCACCAUGCUCUGCUAAUGUAAAAAAGUUUUUUUUUAAUAGAGAAUCUAUUCUUGCUUUUUGCCCAGGCUGGUCUUGAACCCCUGGCCUCAAGCAAUCCUCCCACCUUGGCCUCCCAAAGCACUGGGCUUCCAGGCCUUUUUCUAUGCACAUUUAAGAUUCCGUAUGUAUACACACACACACACAAUGUGUUUUUGAAAAAAAUAGCAUCCUGUUACACAUAUAAAUCUGCACUUUGCUUUGUAUUUUAUGGGCAUCUUUCUGUAUCAUUGCCAAGCAAUCUACCCCAUUCUUUUUGAUGGCUGUAUAGUAUUCCAUCGAAUGAAUGGUGGUUUGUUUAACCAGUCCCUUCUUGAUGGACAUUCAAGAAUAGCAAAAAUGUCUAUUACAAAGCAUGUGGCAGUGCAUAUUUUUGUCCAGCUUCUGUGUACUGAUGCAAAGAUCUCUAGAUUCCUAGAUAGGGUAUUACUGAAUCAAUCAGUUACUUCUGCCCCCUUAGGUAACUCACACCUCCUCAAACACCCCUUUUUUUUUUUUUUUUUCUUUUGAGAUGGAGUCCCACUCUGUCUCCCAGGCUGGAGUGCUGUGGCGUGAUCUCGGCUUACUGCAAUCUCCACCUCCCAAGUUCAAGCGAUUCUCCUACCUCAGCCUCCCCAGUAGCUGGGACUACAGGCACCCGCCACCACACCUGGCUAAUUUUUGUAUUUUUAGUAGAGACUGGGUUUUGCCAUGUUGGCCAGGCUGAUCUCGAACUCCUGACCUCAGGUGAUCCGCCCACCUCGGCCUCCCAAAGUGCUGGAAUUACAGGCAUGAGCCACCGCACCCAGCCCUCAAGCACACGUUUCUACAUGAGAACUUUGUUCUCACCAGUUAGGCAUACAUGCAGGUUGUUGUCAUUGAGAAAGGACAUUCUUCAGUAGGUGACUCAGCUGUAAGAAAAGCAAAUGUAUACCCAGGCUCCCUCAAUAGGAAUAUACUACCUAAAAGGGUGGAGGUGAAAGCCUGCAUUUGGUCAGGCAAACCAUGCCUGGAAUGUUGGGUCCAGUGCUAGAACCAACUAGAGAUAGUGUGGGGUAGAGGGUUGGUGGGGGACUGGAGGGGGGGCAGUCCCUAUGUGGAACAGUAUAGAGAAGGCUGCAGGUUCCAAAUGUCCUCAGGGCUGGCUGUCAUGCUGAAGAUGGGCAUCUUGUUCCUUAUUCCAGGGGACCACAGAGGGGAGAGAAGGGCCAGUGGAAACAGAACUGGGAGCAGCCUAACUGUAGCCAGUGCUGGCUGCCCCAGGAAUUGUUUUGGGGAGGAAGUUGGUGAGAUCUGGAUUGCUAAAGUUGGCCAGCUGGAGUCCCUGGGCUCCUCAGAGGACUGGGUAAGCACAGGAUGGAAUGUCCUCUGAGCUCCCUUCCAGCCUGAGAUUCUAAACCCUGUUGACUGCAGGUGAUGUGGGGCAGAUUGCCACCUGGUUGCAUAUAAAGCUAGAGACAUAUAAAGGCAGGGGCUAGGAACUUGGGGCACGUUCUGGAGAACUGGAAAGUAGGUCUGGUUUCCCACCUCUGAGCUUCAGCCUGCCGCCUCUCCAGGCAGUGUAGAGCAGUGGAAAGGGCACUGAUGUUGGAAUCUGACAGAUUGAGGCUGCAUUAUUUGUUCUACCACUAACCAGCUGUGUAUUCUCAGGCAAAUGACUUAACUUCUCUGAGUCUGCUUCCUCAUCCAUGUAGCUGCGUCGACUGGUUUCCUUGCUGGAAAGUGUGGAUGAUAAUUUCCAUAUCUGUGUGGCAAGAAGAAAAUGAGGUCAUGUGCGUCAUGAUGCGGCCCAGCACCUGGCAUACGGUAGCGCCUAACGAACUGUCACCCUCUCUCCAGCUUAGUUAGGUGCUCUCCAGUCCUCUUUUGCAGUGUGAAUUCUGGCUCAGGUGUUUAGCGGGUGGUGUGUAAUCUGGGCCUCGGAGGCUGAGUGGAGACAGUGGGGCCUUCUUUGUGGGUGACUCGGGAGGGGAGGAUGAAGGACAUGGGAAGAUGUGUGCCAUGUUGAGGAACACAGAUCAGGCUUGGCCAGAGCCUGGUACAAGUUAGGCAGGAGGGGAGGACCUGGCACAGGGCUGCGGAUGUCAGCUGAGGGUCUCUGACUGCCCUCGGGGAGGGGAUAGCACCUAUGAAAGCUCUUAUGGGAGGACUGAUGGGUUAGGGAAAUCCACCUGGGCCUUAGAAGGGAUUGGAGCUGGGGAUUGGAGCCUUCUUAAGGUUAGAAGGUUAAAGAAAGUAGUGCUAAUAAAUUUCAGAUCCUGAAAUGUUAGAACUGGAAGGGGCCUUAAUGAUUAUCCCGCACAACCCCCCAUGUUAUUACUAUUUUUGCAGCUCCCUCUUUUUAGGUAACUGAGGCCUAGUGAGGGUUAAGAUGUUCGCCCUAGUGUACCUUGACUAGAUCCCACAGUUCUGGCGCCCCAGCUGUUACUAUAUGAGACUCUGUGUCUGCAGCCUCAUUGUUGCUCAGUUGAUUGCAAGGAUGGAGGAGUUAAGUCUGGGCUCCUUGUUGGUGAGGAUGCCAGGGUGCGGUCCUUGAAUACACACUGUCUCAAGUAUGUGCUGUGUCCUCACUCAUGUGUGAACCUGACAGCCAUCAGGAGAGCCCAGCCUGGUCCUUUUCUCUUUUAAAUUAAAGACCUUAUUUUUUAUAGAGCAGUUUUAGGUUCACAGCAAAAUUGAGAAGAAGGUACAGAGAUUUUACAUAUACUGCGCCCCCCCCACCCCUAACAGGCAUAGCUUCCCCCAUUAUCAACAUCCUCCACCAGAGUGGUAGAUUUUUUACAGUUGAUGAAUCUACAUUGACACCACUGUCACCCGGAGUCCAUGGUUUACAUCAGUGUUCCCUCUUGGUGGUGUAUGUUCUAUGGGUUUGGACAAAUGUGGAAUGGCAGGUGUCCACCAUUACAGUAUUGAACAGAGUAGUUUCACUGCCUGAAAAAUCCAACCCGGCCUUUGAUGGAUGGACCUGAGGCUGCAGUUUCCCCAGCCUGGAAAUUGGUUGGGGAGGACUGGAGGUCAUCAUAACACAAAUAUGUGGACAGUUUUUUGUUUAUGUCUGCAAUGUGAUAUCAUGGCAUCUCACUUCCUUUCAUCCUUGGGUGGAAUUGCAGGAUAUUGCCCUUUACAGCAGAGGAAAUGAGGCUCAGAUUCCCAGUUGUUGGUGAGUGUGGCAUCGUGGUUCAAGGGCUUCUUAUAGCUACAUGUUCACUAGCUAUGGUGUGUCCAGGCACCCUGCUUAACCACAGUUAAAUGGUGAUAUGCAGGUCACUAGAGAAUAAGUGGAGGCCAGAACCUAGCUUACUGAGCUGACGGAAGAGCCUAAAAUCCCAUUAAAGGAGAGAACAAAUGGGGAAAGCCUUGGCCCUUAGAUAAGCUGGGCACAGUUGUGGGGUUGCCUCAGCCUUUUAUUAAGCACCUGCUGUGUGUCAAAUGCUGAGCUAGUUACUGUAUACUCUUAUUAUUUUGGAAAUCUUAUUAUAAAACAAAGAUGUGUUUCUUGUUAAAUCAGAUAAUCAGGAAGUAUUGCCUAAAGUAGAAAGUGAGAAUUCCCUUCCAACUAUACACAUAUUGUUUCAUUUAAUUUCUUUGAUCUUCUAUCAGGUAGGUUCUAUUAUUACUCCUGCUUUACAGAUGAGGCACCUGAGGCUCAGGAAAGGUGAGUGGCUGCUCCAGGGUUUCACAGCCCACAGGGUGGACAGAGCUGAGGCUAGUGCAGGUGAGGCCCCCUCUCAGGCCUCGUGUUCGCAAGGUUGGCCUUGAGCACUUUCCCUGUGUGGACCUUUCUUCCUGCCUCCAAGGCAGCGAUGUUUCCAUGGUGCUGGCUCUCUCUCUUUCCUCAGCUUGCUGCUAGCUCCUGAGACUUGGGUCUUCUUGAUCCUGAGGCCAGCUUUAGCCAUCACCCGGUUUCUGUGUGGCCCAUGCUCCUCCCCUUGCAUGUGAGGGAAUGAGCCCAUGGUUCCAUACACAGCAGAGUAGACACUAGAAUAGACCUCUCUGACGUUCUGUUCUGUGCCGUCUUUCCUGGAGACCCCUUCCCUAUACCCCCUCUGCCAGCCCACCUGCCAGCAUCCCUGGCAGCCCUCACCUCUGCUGGGGAGGUAGAUGUUGGCCUCGAUGACCUUCCACCUCCCUGUACCAGAGAUUUGCUUACACUUUUCCCUCUGGGCCAGGGAGGGCAUCACCUGCUCCAGGGUUGCAGGGAUAGCUGGCCCCAGGAUGCAGCCAGUGACCAAAGGCAUUAAAUUGGGCUGAUUAAGUCCCCAAGCUGGACUUCAGUUUCCUUAUCCAUCAGGCAGGUAUCAGCCCUGCCUUCUUCCCAGGGCUGUUGUGAUAAUCAGAUGGAAAAACAAUGCUUGGGACACUAUGAAGUAUUUUGCAAAUGUUAGUGGCUAUGCAAGUGAAUAUCAUUUGGGGGGUCUGGGACCACCCCCCUACCCAGCCACCAGAACACUGCUAAUGGGAAGAUAAUCUGACAGACCAAAGCAUUUCAGAGCAAAAGCUAGAAUGUAAAUUUAAUUCUGAAUGUAGUCUUUAUCAUACCCCUCUCUUUCUGGGGUAAGGCUGAGAGUUGAGCCCUGGGGACUACUGCCUCCCUGCCACCCACAAGUGCUUGCCUGCUAGUGGGUGGCUCCUUCGGUUUCAGCAGCAUCACUUCCAUCUUCACGGUCUGUGGUUGUUGCCUGACCUGCCGUCUGUCUGGGCCCCUUUCUGCCCCCAAACUGGGCCUUUCUGGUUCCAGCGGGCAGCCCCAGGGCCCCUCUGGGGCAGGCUGUGGAGGCCCCGCUGGCUGAGGUCUUGUUUUGGAAGAAAGUCUGCGCUGGCUGCUUCUAUACCACCAGCUGUUUCUGGUUUGGGCAAGCGGGGCUGGAGUCCCACUGCUGGUGGAGCACCUGCUGAUUUGUAGUUUGUGGAACCAGGCCAGGUGGAAAGAGACUCUGAGAAGAUGUGGUGGGGGCCUGUGGUGUGCCAUGGGAUUGCUGGGCAGGAAGGGAAAUGGAGGAUGGGCUGUGGGCAGCCUGGAGGGAGAGCAGGGAUCUUCUGGUCCCAGCUCCAUCCUGACUCCUUUGUGACCUUGGCCUUCCCUGCUCAGGGCCUUGCCUUGCUGCACUGCCUGUGCCGUGAGUGAGAAUCAGAUGAGCUCAUGCCCGAGGACUCCUGGGCUCUGAACUCCAGAUACUGCCACAUGGAGGGGAGUGGUCAGUGCUUCCUUUUCCCCUUUGAAAACAUCCUCGUGGUUUGUGGACAGCAGAGGGGAGUGCAUGCCAUCGUCAUGUUCGAAUGCAGCCCCUCAUCCAUUGAGUGUUUCUGGGUGCAUCUCUCUCCCACCUGAUAAUGCAGGAUUCGCCUCAUUGCCCUUGGAGAGUCCCCUCCAGCUCUGUCAUCCUGAGAAUGAGUCCUCUCUCUGGGAGAAGUUAUAAAAACCUCAUUGAUCAGAGGGAGAGUUCCCGUCUGCCCAGUGGUCAUCCAGGGACUGCCGCUGACCAUCUGGGCAUGAGGUCAGCAGAACUUGGAAAUUCCCUGUUUCCCUCUUUGUCUUUCUUUCCUCCAGAAGUCCAGGCCCUCCAGGGGUGGCUCCUCUGAUCUCCAGAGAGGGUUUUCCCACAAUAGGAUAUUUCUCCUGCGUCUCCUCUGCCCACUGCCUUUCUUUCUCCCCAAGCUCUGCCCCCUGAGGCUAAAGUAGGGGAGCAUAGCUCUGUCUGCCCACUUUUUGUUUCCCAUGAACCCCUUUCCCGUUGACUCCCCAGCGCCAAGAGAAACUGAGUGUUGCGUGUUUUGGAGGACGUGGGGUGGGUUUCAGUUCCCACAUCCUGCAUCCUGCUUUGUCCCUUCGCCUUACAUCUGGGCCUCUCUGAGGGAGCAUGGCUGGCCCAGCCUGGAUUCUAGAAGUGUCUGGGCGUCCAAGUGCGUCUGGUCAGUGGGUCAGGGUUAGGCUUUCUCUGGGAUGUUGGACAUGGCCUUGCAGGAGGCGGGGUCGGGGUCAAGGGCUUGUUCCCUUCAGUCUGACUUCUCUGAAUUCAAGGUUUACCGAGGCCCUACUCUGGGCCACUCUGAAGAUACCCUGGCACACAGGAUGGACUUGCUCCCUGUCCUCAUGCAGCCUCUAAUCUACAGGACAAGGCAGACAUUGACCAGGCGGGCACCACGGCAGGGGCUGAGCUACCCUCAUGGAAGGGAGAGGACCGUACCGGAUCUACGACCCUGGGGGCAGCGUGCCCUCAGGAGAGGCAUCCGCAGCUUUUGAGCGCCUAGUGAAGGAGAAUUCCCGGCUGAAGGAAAAAAUGCAAGGGAUAAAGAUGUUAGGGGAGCUUUUGGAAGAGUCCCAGAUGGAAGCGACCAGGCUCCGGCAGAAGGCAGAGGAGCUAGUGAAGGACAACGAGCUGCUCCCACCACCUUCUCCCUCCUUGGGCUCCUUCGACCCCCUGGCUGAGCUCACAGGAAAGGACUCAAAUGUCACAGCAUCUCCCACAGCCCCUGCAUGCCCCAGUGACAAGCCAGCACCAGUCCAGAAGCCUCCAUCCAGUGGCACCUCCUCUGAAUUUGAAGUGGUCACUCCUGAGGAGCAGAAUUCACCAGAGAGCAGCAGCCAUGCCAAUGCGAUGGCGCUGGGCCCCCUGCCCCGUGAGGACGGCAACCUGAUGCUGCACCUGCAGCGCCUGGAGACCACGCUGAGUGUGUGUGCCGAGGAGCCGGACCACGGCCAGCUCUUCACCCACCUGGGCCGCAUGGCCCUGGAGUUCAACCGACUGGCAUCCAAGGUGCACAAGAAUGAGCAGCGCACCUCCAUUCUGCAGACCCUGUGUGAGCAGCUUCGGAAGGAGAACGAGGCUCUGAAGGCCAAGUUGGAUAAGGGCCUGGAACAGCGGGAUCAGGCUGCCGAGAGGCUGCGGGAGGAAAAUUUGGAGCUCAAGAAGUUGUUGAUGAGCAAUGGCAACAAAGAGGGUGCGUCUGGGCGGCCAGGCUCACCGAAGAUGGAAGGGACAGGCAAGAAGGCAGUGGCUGGACAGCAGCAGGCUAGUGUGACGGCAGGUAAGGUCCCAGAGGUGGUGGCCUUGGGCGCAGCCGAGAAGAAGGUGAAGAUGCUGGAGCAGCAGCGCAGUGAGCUGCUGGAAGUGAACAAGCAGUGGGACCAGCAUUUCCGGUCCAUGAAGCAGCAGUAUGAGCAGAAGAUCACUGAGCUGCGUCAGAAGCUGGCUGAUUUGCAGAAGCAGGUGACUGACCUGGAGGCCGAGCGGGAGCAGAAGCAGCGUGACUUUGACCGCAAGCUCCUCCUGGCCAAGUCCAAGAUUGAAAUGGAGGAGACCGACAAGGAGCAGCUGACAGCAGAGGCCAAGGAGCUGCGCCAAAAGGUCAAGUACCUGCAGGAUCAGCUGAGCCCACUCACCCGACAGCGUGAGUACCAGGAAAAGGAGAUCCAGCGGCUCAACAAGGCCCUGGAGGAAGCACUGAGCAUCCAAACCCCGCCAUCAUCUCCACCAACAGCAUUUGGGAGCCCAGAAGGAGCAGGGGCCCUCCUAAGGAAACAGGAGCUGGUCACGCAGAAUGAGUUGCUGAAACAGCAGGUGAAGAUCUUCGAGGAGGACUUCCAGAGGGAGCGCAGUGAUCGUGAGCGCAUGAAUGAGGAGAAGGAAGAGCUGAAGAAGCAAGUGGAGAAGCUGCAGGCCCAGGUCACCCUGUCAAAUGCCCAGCUAAAAGCAUUCAAAGAUGAGGAGAAGGCAAGAGAAGCCCUCAGACAGCAGAAGAGGAAAGCAAAGGCCUCAGGAGAGCGUUACCAUGUGGAGCCCCACCCAGAACAUCUCUGCGGGGCCUACCCCUACGCCUACCCGCCCAUGCCAGCCAUGGUGCCACACCAUGGCUUCGAGGACUGGUCCCAGAUCCGCUACCCCCCUCCCCCCAUGGCCAUGGAGCACCCGCCCCCACUCCCCAACUCGCGCCUCUUCCAUCUGCCGGAAUACACCUGGCGUCUACCCUGUGGAGGGGUUCGAAAUCCAAAUCAGAGCUCCCAAGUGAUGGACCCUCCCACAGCCAGGCCUACAGAACCAGAGUCUCCAAAAAAUGACCGUGAGGGGCCUCAGUGAGACCAGAUUGUGUCAUUUGGCUCCACCUUCAUCUUGCAGAGCCAGCUGAUCUCAGAUUGCCAAGAAACUAGAAGCCACUUGCACGGUGUGGCCAGAGCCUCAGCUGGAUGAGAGGCUGAGAUGGGUGGCCAGCUUGUACACCAGUCCCUGAACUGAGCUGUUUACAGGACUGGGGAGGCUCCACCCAGAAGGCUUUCAUUUGUACUCUGCUGGGAGUGACUGGGAAAAACUCCUUCCCUGCUGCUGAGUGGAGAGAGGCCUCAUCCGGCUUUGACCCACCAUCCGUUGCAGAAGCCUCCAGGAGCAGCAAUCCUAAGAGUGGGAGGCAGCCAAGACCCCCUUCCUUCAAAACCUCCCGGAAGUGGUUUCAGGCCCUCUAGUUGCCAUGACCAAUUUGUGUGUGUGUUUAAUUUUUGCUUCAAGCUCUGUAGCAGGACCUGCCCCACGCACACCCCUACCCCUCUGUGAGGAGCUGUGGGAAGUGUGGGUUUGUCUCCAGAACAGAAGAGAAUGAUGGAUAUUCUGGCUCUGGGGCCCUCUCCACCACCACUCACAGUAGCCUUGCUGAAGCCAUCACAGAUGGGAGAAGGCCAUGCCAGCCACGUCCGCCGAGGGGCGCCAGCCUGAAGCUGCCAGGCCCUGAGGUUCAGACCCUGGACCCCAUAGCUGGAGGCCUGUGGUGCCAGAAGCCCAGAUUAGGGUGGCUGUCCAUCCCUGGAUAGCUAUUUGCACGAAUCAUGGACAUAAAUCCAAGUUGAAGAAGAUCAACA